UGAAUUUGUUGCUCCAAGGGCCACUGAAGCAAAGAAUACAGUGAUUUGGUUUGAAACUCACAAGGCUCGACCUUUAGAAUGAAAUUUCUCAUCUUGGCUGGCCUUUUGAGCACUGCCACUGCUCUGCCCAUCCCCCUCGAACAAUAUGCUGAAAGUUCCAGUGAACAGAGAUUUAUCUUUUACCCACCACAAGUACCACCAUUUUUCCCUCAGGUCCUCUUUCCCCUACCUCCGCAACCGCCCCUGGUCCUCACACCUAAUGAUCUUAUCGCGUUACUCAUUGCUAUUUUGAACCAACUAGGGAUUUUAUUUCCAUGACUAAAUUGAUAAAGAAAUAAUUCUCCCACUACUAUGCCAGAAGUUACGUAUGAUGGUGCUGGAUAUUUACAGUUAUCAGAAGAGUAUCUACUUCUAUCUUAACUAUAGUUGAUGGUAGUUUUAUAAUUUUGCAUACUUUGUGCAUGUUCCAGUGAAAACUCCAAAAAACCAUAAAGAAUGUAUCUAGACCAUGGGCUUUAGUCAUACUUUAAAUAAACCUUUAAUAUAACCAAA